AGACACGAAGCCUCCCGGGUGGCUUACAGACGCUGCCAGCAUCGCCGCCGCCAGAGGAGAAAUGUCUGAAGUAAGACCCCUCUCCAGAGACAUCUUGAUGGAGACCCUCCUGUAUGAGCAGCUCCUGGAACCCCCGACCAUGGAGGUUCUUGGCAUGACUGACUCUGAAGAGGACCUGGACCCUAUGGAGGACUUCGAUUCUUUGGAAUGCAUGGAGGGCAGUGACGCAUUGGCCCUGCGGCUGGCCUGCAUCGGGGACGAGAUGGACGUGAGCCUCAGGGCCCCGCGCCUGGCCCAGCUCUCCGAGGUGGCCAUGCACAGCCUGGGUCUGGCUUUCAUCUACGACCAGACUGAGGACAUCAGGGAUGUUCUUAGAAGUUUCAUGGACGGUUUCACCACACUUAAGGAGAACAUAAUGAGGUUCUGGAGAUCCCCGAACCCCGGGUCCUGGGUGUCCUGCGAACAGGUGCUGCUGGCGCUGCUGCUGCUGCUGGCGCUGCUGCUGCCGCUGCUCAGCGGGGGCCUGCACCUGCUGCUCAAGUGAGGCCCCGGCGGCUCAGGGCGGGGCUGGCCCCACCCCCAUGACCACUGCCCUGGAGGUGGCGGCCUGCUGCUGUUAUCUUUUUAACUGUUUUCUCAUGAUGCCUUUUUAUAUUUAAACCCCGAGAUAGUGCUGGAACACUGCUGAGGUUUUAUACUCAGGUUUUUUGUUUUUUUUUUAUUCCAGUUUUCGUUUUUUCUAAAAGAUGAAUUCCUAUGGCUCUGCAAUUGUCACCGGUUAACUGUGGCCUGUGCCCAGGAAGAGCCAUUCACUCCUGCCCCUGCCCACACGGCAGGUAGCAGGGGGAGUGCUGGUCACACCCCUGUGUGAUAUGUGAUGCCCUCGGCAAAGAAUCUACUGGAAUAGAUUCCGAGGAGCAGGAGUGCUCAAUAAAAUGUUGGUUUCCAGCA